AACCGUAGCGACGCCGGCCCUGGCUGAGAGGCGUUAGGAGUCCGGGGGUUCGCCCGCGGAGGCCGGGGAGCAGCCGACCAUGGAGCCCCAGAAAAUCAUGCCACCCUCAAAGCCUCAUCCACCUGUCGUGGGCAAAGUGACUCAUCACAGCAUUGAAUUAUACUGGGAUCUGGAAAAGAAAGCCAAACGCCAAGGACCUCAAGAGCAGUGGUUCAGGUUCUCGAUUGAAGAAGAAGACCCCAAAAUGCACACUUAUGGUAUCAUUUAUACGGGAUAUGCAACGAAGCAUGUUGUUGAAGGUCUGGAACCAAGGACGCUGUACAGAUUUCGCCUGAAGGUCACCAGCCCCUCUGGGGAGUGUGAGUACAGCCCACUCGUCUCAGUGUCUACAACCAGGCCAUCUCUGAGCAAGAGCCUUGUAAAAAUUAGGAUGGUCACAAGUGUUCUCCACGGCCCACCCACUGAAAACACAGGAGAGCCCAUAAGUAGUGAGCACUUGCACCGGGCUGUCAGUGUGAAUGAUGAAGAUUUGCUGGUCCGAAUACUUCAAGGAGGCCGUGUUAAGGUUGAUGUUCCCAAUAAGUUUGGCUUUACCGCUCUGAUGGUUGCUGCCCAGAAAGGAUACACCAGGCUUGUGAAAAUCCUAGUUUCUAAUGGCACAGACGUGAAUCUGAAGAAUGGAAGUGGCAAGGACAGUCUAAUGCUGGCGUGCUAUGCGGGACACCUAGAUGUUGUGAAAUAUCUCCGAAGACAUGGCGCUUCUUGGCAGGCUAGAGACCUGGGAGGCUGUACAGCUCUGCACUGGGCUGCAGAUGGAGGCCACUGCAGUGUGAUUGAGUGGAUGAUAAAGGAUGGCUGUGAGGUAGACGUCGUGGACACUGGUUCAGGAUGGACCCCACUCAUGAGAGUCUCUGCGGUGUCGGGAAAUCAGAGGGUGGCCUCUCUUCUAAUUGAUGCUGGGGCCAAUGUGAAUGUGAAGGACAGAAAUGGAAAGACGCCCCUUAUGGUGGCUGUGUUAAAUAAUCAUGAAGAGUUAGUUCAGUUACUUCUUGACAAAGGGGCAGAUGCAAGUGUAAAAAAUGAGUUCGGCAAAGGUGUCCUAGAAAUGGCCAGAGUUUUUGACAGACAGAGUGUAGUCUCCUUAUUAGAAGAAAGGAAAAAAAAGCAGAGGCCAAAGAAGUCUUGUGUCUGCUGAUGAGAGCACCACUCAUCUGCGAAACGCACGUAAAACAAAGUGAACCGUGACUGUUAAACUAGGGAUGGGAAAUUCUGCAUCUUGGGGGGCUGUACAUUUAUUUAUUUAGUUGAAGAUUCACUGAUCCCACUUUGAAAUACAUCUUUUUACCUAA